GAUCUGCCCACCUCAGUCUCCCAAAGUGCUGAGAUUACAGGCGUGAGCCACUGCACCCCACCAGAAGCCUCUUUUUUAAUGAUUAGGGCCAAUUAAUCCUUUCAGAUGGUGACACCUUUUCUUGCUGCUGGUUGUAUGGCAAAAGAAGCCUGAAGUGUCAGGGAGGCAGUCCCAGCUUAAUGUGUAAUGAGACUCUCGCUGUGUCCCUUAGUGGGAAAAGUCCCCCUCUGGGGAGCUGCAACGAUGGGAAGCACAGUUCUCUAAGUGAGCCACUGGGAGCAAUCAUAAGUAGGGCAGCACUCCUUCCAGCCACUGAAUCCCAUACUCAUGGUAGACCUUCUGGGGACACAAUACCAUGCCUUUGUUAUUGAUUUCAAGAGAAUAUUGCAUCUUGGAGUGUAGUGCCCCAUCCUUGCAGGAGAUUAUCUCCAAGCUGUAUCCUCAAAGGGUAGCUUCUUUGAGCUAUCAGGACAGAAGCUCCAGGGCAGUGCGGGAUGUGAUAGGACUGGUGAACCCAUGCUCACUUGCACGCUGUCAAACUUCUUUUGCUGUGAAGCGGGUCCCUGGGUCCAAAGGCAAGUCGUGCAGGAUUCACGUGGGUGGACCAGACGUUUUGUAAACCCUCGGAUAGUGAUGGUGCCUGAAGUUCUGUGGAAAGGAAAGCCAAACUCCCACCAGGAUAUGAGUUAAUUCCUGUCAAGCAGAAUCAUUCCCUUCCAGACUGGCUGGUUGGUCUCUGAGUGAUUGUGCCAUACUGGGGGCUCAGGGUUGUUCUCUGUGGCUUGCAGGUUGGGUAUUUAGUAGCUAGAUCAGCCUUGGUGAGUUGGAGACCAUGCUGUUGGGUCCAUGCAUAGCCUCCUUCCCUGUCACCACAGCUGCUUCGUUCAUGGGUUCAUUGGGCCACUACUGGAGUGAGCAGUGAGUGAGGAGGGCUGAACCUCGGCUGGCUGAGUCAUUCUCCCUCCUUGUUGUUUGAUGUCUCUUCCACGGUGAAUGCUGUCUUGGGGAAACUAACAUAGAACAUGACCAUCUUUAUGUUUAAUGCUCAUCCUGACAGGACCAUUCACAGGCCUCCUUGUCCCAAACUUUGAAUUUUUCUUCUUGUAAGUCACUCAACAACCAGCCAAGCCAUUCACCACUGCCAGUGAAUCUAUAUGUGUUUUAACCUCGGGCCACUUUUGUUUCCGCUCCAAGUAGAUGACAUUGGGAAGAAGUCCCUCAUUACGUCUUUCAGGGGCACCCUGAAUUAUCAGGGGCUGUAGUGCAGGAAUAGUCCAUUUUCAGCUAGUACCAUGUAGCAAGUUUACCCAUCUGCCAUCUGUGAACCAAGCAUUUCCCUCCCUGCUCAGCAGGUAAAAAGGGACAAGCCCCUUUCCCUGCCACCGUGUGGUCACAGGAGUUAACUGAAGGGAAAGCACUGGUUAGAAGUGGUGGAUGACAGGCAGGGCUGGGUGUGGGAGAGUGUCUCGGACACCUGCCACUGCAACUUACAAGUGCCUUCUGGCCCUACUGGUGCUCCAUCAUGAGAAUUAUUUGCAGAUUGCUUGUCUGACCUUAUGAGUUAGGGGGUCCUGACCUGAACCCAGGUCAUGGUGGGCUGGCUGCAUGGUCCUUGUUGCCAUGGUUAGGUAGCAGGACAAAGCUUUUUUCAAAUAGUGCAUAUUUUUCUGCUGCUAAUGAUGUGAGCUUGCUCUAGACCUAAGGGUCUGUGCUGUGAUUCUCCUGUUGAGACUUGUCUUAACUGCCACCUGGUGUCUUUUCCCACUAGGGCCUGCCGGGCUGUAUGGGCCCAACAGCAGGGACACUUGCACCUCAGCCUGGACCUGCUGCCCUGCUCUUCCUUCUCUGGGUCUCAUGCAAAACUGGCAUCUUUCAUGUCGCAGGAUAAGUGUGUUUCAGCAAUGUUCCCAAGGGUGGGAAAUGCUGCCUCCAGAAUCCAGAGAAGUCUGCUGGGCCUUGUGCUUCCUUCUUAAAGGUGGGAGGUGUAAGGUGCAAUAAUUUUAUGUUUUACUUUAGAGGGAAUGUCCCAGCAAGCCCCAGACCACUGGAUCCUUACAAACAUACUGAUCUAUGGGGUUCCUGAUCUUCAUAGGGUUUCUCUCUUAUCUUUCUUCCCACCUCCUGGCAACAUACUUGUUGCAUUUUGUUCAUUCAGCCUUAAUGUGUCCACAUAGUGGACCAACAUGAUGCACUGUGGAAUGUCCACAAGGUCCCGGUCUUUUCAGCCUGUAUCCUGACAGAGAGCUGGAGAAUUAACAUCGCCCUGGGAAGAGCUGUGAAUGAGUACUGCUAUCCAUCCCACGUGAGCGCGAGCUGCUCCUACUCCUCUCUGCUGAUAAAGAGGAGAAACCGCAUUCAUCGGUUGCUUGGCUGUGUGCCUUGUCUAUGGUCACUGGCUCUAGAAAAAGUUCUACAUGGGCUCAGCAGCUGUGCUUGGGACUACACUUAGAGAUCAAGUUAAAGAAUAAUCCUUGGUAAAUCUUGGCUGCGGGUGACUGAUGGAAGUUUCAGAGGCUGGACUGGAAGAUGAAACUGGGGCAAGAUGUUACACAGCAUGGCCUCAGGAACCUGAGCUCCAGCAACCUGCGGGUCCCAAUGGAGGCGAAGUCAAGGAGCGUCUCAGAGAGUGGUUGAUGUGUGAAGUCUCUGUCUGCCCAUCUGAAUAACAAGAGAUGGGGCUUGUGAUUUUCCUCCACGCACCCCUACCUGAGGGCCUCCAGGAGGAAUGACAUCUCAAACAGAAACCUGCAUAACAUCAGCCCAAACCAAGGACCCAUUUUAUCAUCAAAGAGGUGUGCCAUGAAUGCAUGACUGUGGGAUCCACUGCUUUGACCACAUAUGGAUGACUUGGAAGCUGCCAGCCUACAUGAACAAUGGAAAGGCCAUUGAUGGCUCAGCAAAGUUGCCAGCUGAGGGCCAAUGCUCCCCAGGGUUGGCCUCGAGGGUGGCCACAGUGCUGUAACAACAGCCAGUGUGGUGCUGAACCUGCAGCCUACCUAUGAUGCUUUGACACCAAUUGUCAGGACACACGGGUCUGGAAACCAAAUCUUGGAAGUAGGAUUGGUUGCUUUCCGUGUAACUCCUAGUGACCCACUAGUAGAAUUUUGCUUCCUAUCCCUGAGAACUUAUAUUCCACAGGACUAGAGAUCCUGGUUCCUGGGAUGAAGCAGGGCAGCUUCUGCUGAGGUUCACAGUAAAGGUUCUGUUGAACCCAAAUAUGACUAUCACUGGGUCCCUUUGGGCCCACUAGUGGACGAGCAGGCAAAGAAAGAAGUUACUCCACCAUCAGGGGACAGAUAAUUCCAGCUCUCAAUGGGGCUAUGGUUGCUACCAGGGGACUGAAACACAGCUGAGACUGAGGAGAUUGUCGGUGGCUUCUUCUGGUGCUUCCAAGUCUGGGGAUAAUGAUGACUGGGCAGCCAUCAGAGCCUGAUAAACACAAGGCAACCAAGAGCUCAGACCCUGAGCGGUGAAAAGGCCAGCCAGUGCUCAGGCAGGUCACCCAGACCAUCAUAAGCGCUGAUAGAAAUCUAGGACGUGCGGUGGAGGAGGGAGAUGACACGUCCCAACCAUGGUCCCUGGUUAGCUGCAGGUGGCGUGUCCACCACGCCUUCUCUUUGGAGUCAUUUGGAGAUGGUGGCUGGCCACGAUCUUGCAGGCUUAGUGACAGAACAAUCUGAGAAGAACGAGGGGGGGAGCUGCUGCAGACCCAUGUGGUGCUCUGCCUCAUGCCCUCUCAGCCUAACCUCUAAUUUCAGCAGAGAUGGGGUGUGUUUCUGUUCCGUGGUUAAGUCGCUGCAUGCUCACAGAGGCUUACUUCAAGCACGGGCUGCAAGGUUUUACUUUCUUCAUCAGGAUUCCUCUCAUGCCACGAAUGGGGAAAGUUCACAGUUGUUGGAGCUGAUAUUCCUAGAGAAAAAUGCUGGUUCUGGGUCUGGUAAUGAAGUCAUAGAAGGCCCCCAAAAUGCAAGAGUCCUGAAGGGCUCCCAGGCUCGCUUCAACUGCACCGUCUCCCAGGGCUGGAAGCUCAUCAUGUGGGCUCUCAGUGACAUGGUGGUGCUAAGCGUCAGGCCCAUGGAGCCCAUCAUCACCAAUGACCGCUUCACCUCUCAGAGGUACGACCAGGGCGGGAACUUCACCUCGGAGAUGAUCAUCCACAAUGUGGAGCCCAGUGAUUCGGGGAACAUCAGAUGCAGCCUCCAGAACAGUCGCCUGCAUGGAUCUGCUUACCUUACCGUCCAAGUUAUGGGAGAGCUGUUCAUUCCCAGUGUUAAUCUUGUAGUCGCUGAGAAUGAACCUUGUGAAGUUACUUGUCUACCCUCACACUGGACCCGGCUCCCGGAUAUUUCCUGGGAGCUCGGUCUCCUGGUCAGCCAUUCAAGCUAUUAUUUUGUUCCGGAGCCCAGCGACCUUCAAAGUGCAGUGAGCAUCCUGGCUCUGACCCCACAGAGCAAUGGGACUUUGACUUGCGUGGCUACCUGGAAGAGCCUGAAGGCCCGCAAGUCUGCAACUGUAAAUCUCACUGUGAUUCGGUGUCCCCAAGACACUGGAGGUGGUAUUAAUAUUCCAGGUGUAUUAUCAAGUUUACCGAGUUUAGGUUUUUCAUUGCCUACUUGGGGCAAAGUUGGACUUGGACUAGCAGGCACCAUGCUUCUGACGCCGACGUGUACUCUUACAAUACGCUGCUGCUGCUGCCGCCGUCGUUGUUGUGGCUGCAACUGCUGCUGCCGUUGUUGUUUCUGCUGUAGAAGAAAAAGAGGAUUUCGUAUUCAAUUUCAAAAGAAAUCUGAAAAAGAGAAGACAAACAAAGAAACUGAGACAGAAAGUGGAAAUGAAAACUCCGGCUACAAUUCAGAUGAACAAAAGACCACAGACACCGCUUCUCUCCCUCCCAAAUCCUGUGAAUCCAGUGAUCCUGAACAAAGAAACAGUAGCUGUGGCCCUCCUCACCAGCGGGCUGAUCAACGUCCACCCAGGCCAGCAAGUCAUCCACAGGCUUCUUUUAAUCUGGCCAGUCCUGAGAAGGUCAGUAAUACAACUGUAGUAUAGCAAAGCCUUCCCCAAGCUCCACUGAGCACUUGGCUGACAAUUCAAAACACGGCGAUGGCAUCCUUCCUUUCCAUCCUAAGACUGGCCUGCAGCUUUGCCAACAUUACCUGAAGAGGAGAUGUCGGAGUCAUCAGAACUGAUACUUGACAGUGAGAGAAGGAAUCGAUUUUCCCAGAGUUCAAAGUAGAAUGUGACUUUUAAGAGGUUUCAUGGUUUUUGUGAAUUCCAUGAAGUUACUAAGUAAAAGCUGCAAAUUCAUCAUAAUUUUUCUCAACAUUCAACACUCCUACUUGUUAAUCCAACAAAUGGUAGAUAAAAGUCUGUAUUCUACCAUGCCUUUCAAAAGUUUUUAUUAUCUGAAAGCAUAUGAAGAUGAUAUUUAUGUAUAUUUAAUAUGUAGGGGUAUUAUUACAUAUUAUCAGUGAAAUACGAGUAUAAAAAUUAGGGUCAACCAGAAAUCUGCAAUUGACUGUCAAAACUGAGCUCAGUUAAAGUAAGAUUCAAUUCUAACAUGGAUGUGCACGUUCCUAAAUAUCUUAUGAUUGAAUAUUUACAUGAAGGCAUUCAUUUUUAUCUGCCCCUUUAUCAGACCUAUUUGCAUCUCCUCAAAUGAAUUAGAUGUGGCCUAUGCUUUGCAGAGGAUGGACCUCACCUACUCCGCACACCGUGAAAAAACUGGAAAUGGGCAUUGUAGUCUUUAAUUAAUAAAAACACCAAAAAUGUG